ACAGCUGCCUGGGUAAGGCCCAAGAUGGCUGUCUUCGCCUUAGUACUCGUGUGAAGUUGGCGGGGACGGUUCCUGUCAUCUUCUUGGGCUUAUUUGGUGUGCUGUUGAAGGGGGGAGACUAGAGAAAUGGCAGGGAACCUCUUAUCCGGGGCAGGUAGGCGCCUGUGGGACUGGGUGCCUCUGGCGUGCAGAAGCUUCUCUCUUGGUGUGCCUAGAUUGAUCGGUAUAAGGCUCACUCUCCCGCCCCCCAAAGUGGUUGAUCGUUGGAACGAGAAAAGGGCCAUGUUCGGAGUGUAUGACAACAUCGGGAUCCUGGGAAACUUUGAAAAGCACCCCAAAGAACUGAUCAGGGGGCCCAUAUGGCUUCGAGGUUGGAAAGGGAAUGAAUUGCAACGUUGUAUCCGAAAGAGGAAAAUGGUUGGAAGUAGAAUGUUCGCUGAUGACCUGCACAACCUUAAUAAACGCAUCCGCUAUCUCUACAAACACUUUAACCGACAUGGGAAGUUUCGAUAGAAGAGAAAGCUGAGAACUUCGGAAAAGGCUCAUCUGUCACCCUGGAGAAGGGAAACUGUACUUUUCCCUGUGAGGAAACGGCUUUGUAUUUUCUCUGUAAUAAAAUGGGGCUUCUUUGGAAUUUGAUAGCCACAUACUUUUGUUUUCCUCUAGAUGCUGCCUCUACUCAUGUAGACUAUGAAGUCUUGACUCAUCCUAGAUCUUAGGAUCUUAGGUUUGGGCUUCACACCACUUGCCUUUUACAGUCUAGCUAUACCUAAUUCCUUUAAAAAGAAAAGUUGGUGAGAAUGUUAUUGGCGCUUUUUGACAUAAUGCUGUUAUGUUAAUAGUGUUUCUAAAGAGCCUUCCACACUGAAAUGAAAUAUAAGAGAAAAAUGGAGUCAUA